GCUCCAUCGGGUCUGGCGGGGCUGGCAGCGGCGAGGACCCGGGUCUGGCGCUGUGGGCCGGGAGCCGUGGGGCGGCAUGGAGGGGCUGGUUGUCGCCGCCGGCGGGGACGUCUCCCUGCACAACUUCAGCGCGAGGCUGUGGGAGCAGCUGGUCCACUUCCACGUCAUGCGGCUGACGGACUCGCUGUUCCUGUGGGUGGGGGCCACGCCGCACCUGCGCAACCUCGCCGUGGCCAUGUGCAGCCGCUACGACUCCAUCCCCGUGUCUACCUCCCUCCUUGGAGACACUUCCGACACGACCUCUACUGGCCUUGCCCAGCGCCUAGGUAUGUACCCACAGCUGGCGCUGCAUGGCCAGCCAGGUGGGGCCCACUCUUUAAUGGAACCAUGAAGCAAGUCCCUUCGGAAGUAAAGCAUCUUUAUGCUAAGAACCAUCACCUCAUUGCUGCUGGGAAGCACAGACCUUUGCACGUUGGGUCUUAUUUAAGGGGCACAUUCCAUGCUCGCCUGUCAUCACCACCGUCCCAGGGCUGGCCUGUUCCCAAAGGACUCCCACCUCGUCCUUGGGUGUGUCCUUGAGUCCAUGAGCUGAUUUAGUUGCCUUCCGUAAGUGCAUCACCACCUCCUGGGAGGAGAGCAUGAGAAGUGCCCACAGCCCCUGUGGGUGGUGGCUCAAGGUAGCCUCCCGGGCCUUAGGAGGAGUCAGUGCAGCUGGUGGAGCAGGUGUCACCUCUGUGCAGGAAGGACUGUCCUCACUCAGUGUGAUACCGUUCAGGGCUCGGAGGGAAGACUGGCCUGGCCUGUGAGUGUGGCGUAGAGUGGGGAUUAAGCAAAGGUCAUGAGGCUGAAUGCUCCACUCUUCCCACACCCCAACACACUUCCUGUGGGCCAGGUAAGGCUUCCAUGUGCUCUGCGACCCCCAGCCCCAGUGCCUGUGGCCAGUGUGCACAGGAUGCCUGUCUCCUGCCCAGGCCUGGCGUUCUCCAGUAGGCCCAGCUGCUUCUGCUCUGGAGUCUUCUCUGUGUCUCAGGCACAGGACCUGGUACCUGACAAGCAGGAACCUCUGUGUCAGUCACACUGAGGCAAAUGCACACGAAUAGCAUGGCACCUGGCCCAGGGGGAAGGCAGGGCAGGGUGGAGUGUCACCAGCAGGCCCAUGACAGUAUGUGGAUAGGACAGAGGUCAGGGAGGGCACAGGUCAGCAUUUCAGGAACUCGCAGUAUUCUUUUUCCCUCCCUUGGAGGUGGGGACCUGACUUGUAAGUUAAUUUGGUAAUUUUUAACUAGGAAGUAAAUUUAAAAUUUACAGAAAAGUUGCAAAGAAGAUAGAAUUCCUGCUUAGCUUUUGCCCCAAUUUCCCACUUGCCACCCUUCCCUCUUUGUGUUUGUAUCUUUUUUUUUCUGAGCCACAUGAAAGUAAAGCUGCCUUUUGUGUCUGUGUCACUCUGUGUGUGUGACUGUGUAAGGGGUAGCACACUUACAUGGAACAGGUUACUGCGUGUGGGAGAAGGCUCAGGAAGGUAUUCAUAUUUAUACAGACGGAAAGCUGGGUGGGGUUGCGGACACACUCCCAUAGAGAAGGUGGUGUGAGCUUGUCUGGCAGGCCGUGAAUAACUUUCAUAUCAAUAAGGUAAAUUAGUCUCCAGAAUAUUUGCGAGAUGGAGGCCUAGUAUCUAUAUGCAAAAAAGAGGGGUUCUCAGUAUCUCGACUGUCUCAACAAGUCACGGGUGUGCCGUGGCUUCCGGCGUCUCUUAAGGGAAUGGUGCUGCAGAGCUCGGACCAAGAAGGUUUUCCAGCAAAGUCCCAUGCUUUGCCAGUUGCCUUGAGCCUGGGUCUGGGCCCUCAAGUUGAAAAUGCACUAUAAUGAAAAGGGAGAGGUGUCCUGAAUCAGUAUCUUAUAUGAGAGAUGAAAGCAGGUAGGGAAAGAGAAGGCCUGGGGGGUUCUCAGUAGCUCUGGAAGCAUCGCAGGAGUUGGUGUGGCCAAGGGGACCCAACCUCCUAUGGCCCUGGAGGGGCACAGCUUGGGUCUGAGGGGCUCAGUGCCUCCAGACACAGCGUUGUUCCUCAGAAAUCCUGUCUCUGCAGUUAGAACAGUUGGAAUACCAGGGGGGCCCCCUUAGGGUAAAGGGGGAUGUUCCUGCCCCUGGGAUAUAGGGCAGGGUGUGACUUACAGGCUCCUCCUAGGCAGCCUUGGUGAGCCCCAGCUUCCUACCACACUGCCUGCCUUUAGAUCACCCUCUACAUGAGUGGUCCCAGCCUGCCUAACACAGCUAGGAAAGGAUGAGGUUGGUCCCUAAUGGUGGGGGAAGCCUAAGAGGCUUCCUCACUCCCCGCAGGGCUGAGCAGAUAACUGGGCACAACUCUCCGCCUCGGGGGCACACUGCACCCAGCACACUGGUGGGAGGCUCUGUGCUAAGUACUGUAAGCUGUUCUUUAAACACCAGCUCUUGGAAUAACCGAACAGCUGCCUUUGUCCGGACACAUUCCUUUUUUUUUUUUUUUAAUAAAAAAACAGCUUUACCGAGACGUAAACACAUGUCAUACAAUUCAGCAGCUGUCCUCAGGCAGAGGCUGUGCUUGCCGCCGCCUUGCUUUUUCAUAGGUGUGUUGGCUGCUUUGUAAGGACAGUCAGUGAGUUAAUACCCAAGACCUUUCCAGCCCUAAAAAUCACGCAGCCUUGUACAGCGGAAAAACAGGCUUUUGGGGUCCUGGGCUCUCCCUCUCCUCAAUUUCCAAACAAAGCUGGGAGAGGUUUCCAGGCCACGGUGGGGCCUGGGCCUGCGCCUGCACCUGCGCCCCUGAGCCACACUGCCUCUCAGGGUUCUUGGUGGGACCAUAGCUCAGAUGGCAGCAACUGAAAGGACAGAACUGCUGCCCAGAUGAGAUCCCAUGACGUGUGUUCUAAAUCGGCCUUUAGUAAUGGUGCAGGUGGCCUGGUGCCCUCAGCCUCACCGCACCACCCUUUUGCCUUUUGGUGAUGAGGCUAAGUACAUGCUUGCCAUAUGUUGAGGUGGGGGUGGGUCAGUGCCUCUCCAGGGGUGAGUAGUUCUGCACUGGCCCUGCGUAUGGGUGAGGCUAAAGGAGGAGGCCGCGCAGUGGGGCAGGCAACAUCCAACUGCUUUAGCCUUUUUGCCCACGUAUUUUCAGGAUAUUGGCUUUCAGAUUCCAGGUGUAUGACUCUGCUUGAUUUUUGCAGUUGGCCCAAUGUGCACCUCAGCCAUUUUCUAUUGAUUCUGUAGAAGGGGACUAAAACUUACAUUCAGUAGAAAAUUACGUGUGUGUCCAUAUGCCUAUCUGUGCACACACACACAAAUAUAUUUGUGUGUAUACACAUAUAUGCAAAUGCAUGGAAACGUAGGAGGGAGGGAAGUGGAACUGGUUGGGGUGGGGUGGUGCUGAAGGAGAACUUUAAUAUUUUAUUUUAAAUACUUAUUUUUUUUUGAGACGGAGUCUUGCUCUAUUGCCCAGGCUGGAGUGCAGUGGCGCGAUCUUGGCUCACUGCAAGCUCCGCCUCCCGGGUUCACGCCAUUCUCCUGCCUCAGCCUCCCGAGUAGCUGGGACUACAGGCGCCCGCCACCAUGCCCGGCUAAUUUUUUGUAUUUUUAGUAGAGACGGGGUUUCAACGUGUUAGCCAGGAUGGUCUCGAUCUCCUGACCUUAUGAUCCACCCGUCUCGGCCUCCCAAAGUGCUGGGAUUAUGGGCGUGAGCCACCGCUCCCGGCCAUUUUUUGUGUUUAAAUUUUUUUUUUUUUUUUUAAAUCAAAACACCAGAAACCCCUCUGUGUAGGGCAGAGGUUCUUAAGCAGUGCGGGGCACCUGCAGGAUCUGUUCCAGCAGACAGCUGGCCCCAAAUCCUGGCUUUCUGGGUCAGGAGGGCUGGGUGGGGCCCAGCAGCUGCCUCUCGAACAAGUUCCAGGGAGGCUGCUGAGGUGGGGCCUGCCCUUCAGAACCCUGGGUCUGGUGGAGAGACUGGGAGAGGCCUGAGUGACUCGUCUGCAUUUGCAGCACCUGUCUGAAGAGAGGCAUGGAGAUUAGAGCUUUCUUUUCUCCCUACAACCCCAUCCUCUUUCUGAGCAUUUCCCAGCUGCACGUGGCUGUGAGGAACACGGGGCCUGCAGUAUUUCAGGAGUGGCUGUAUCAAUGUGUUUUCUCUUUUUAGCCAGGAAGACCAACAAACAGGUGUUUGUCAGCUAUAACCUUCAGAACACAGACAGUAACUUCGCAUUACUUGUAGAAAACAGGAUCAAGGAAGAGAUGGAGGCUUUCCCCGAAAAGUUCUAGCUGAGUGGCAGAAGUGAGAAUUUGUAAACUUAUGUACAAUGUACGUGUAAAUAAAUGGAUUGAAUUUCAGUUUGUCAUCAGGCCGCGCUCCCGUUUUGUUUUUAAGGGGUUAAUCUUUUGAGCUUCCUUCUCAGCAGUGUGUGGGCCAAAAGGCUCAUACUGACCCACCUGGUGAAGGAGAGGCAAAGUGGGCAGUAUAUACUUCCUCAUUUGGCUGUGAGUGAUAGAGGGAUGAAAUGGGAUUUUUGUUGGGAUUGAAGACUGUAAUCUAAGAGUUUCAAUCAGACAUGACUGUGACGUGCAUCCUCAAUUAGAAUUAAAGUGAUGUAUAAAUAUG